GCUGGAGUUUGAAGAGCGGGCAGUGGCUGCACACGCCAAACUUUCCCUAUGGCUUCGGUGACCAGGGCCGUGUUUGGAGAGCUGCCCUCGGGAGGAGGGACAGUGGAGAAGUUCCAGCUGCAGUCAGACCUCUUGAGAGUGGACAUCAUCUCCUGGGGCUGCACGAUCACAGCCCUAGAGGUCAAAGACAGGCAGGGGAGAGCCUCGGACGUGGUGCUUGGCUUCGCCGAGUUGGAAGGAUACCUCCAAAAGCAGCCAUACUUUGGAGCAGUUAUUGGGAGGGUGGCCAACCGAAUCGCCAAAGGAACCUUCAAGGUGGAUGGGAAGGAGUAUCACCUGGCCAUUAACAAGGAACCCAACAGUCUGCAUGGAGGAGUCAGAGGGUUUGAUAAAGUGCUCUGGACCCCUCGGGUGCUGUCAAAUGGCGUCCAGUUCUCGCGCAUCAGUCCAGAUGGUGAAGAAGGCUACCCCGGAGAGUUAAAAGUCUGGGUGACAUACACCCUGGAUGGCGGAGAGCUCAUAGUCAACUACAGAGCACAAGCCAGUCAGGCCACACCAGUCAACCUGACCAACCAUUCUUACUUCAACCUGGCAGGCCAGGCUUCCCCAAAUAUAAAUGACCAUGAAGUCACCAUAGAAGCGGAUACUUAUUUGCCUGUGGAUGAAACCCUGAUUCCUACAGGUGGCACCAACAGAAGGUUUCUGCAAGGCUGAGAGCUCCUUUUACCCAUGGACCAGGAGCAAAGUUUGCAGGCUGUGUGCGGUGGCUCAUGCCUGUAAACCCAGCACUUUGGGAGGCCGAGGUGGACUGAUCACCUGAGGUCAGGAGUUCAAGACCAGCCUGGACAACAUAGCAAGAACCAUCUUAAAAAAGAAAAGAGAAGAAUAUUUAAAAUUUUCUUCACUGAUCAUUCAGGAGCAUAUUGUUUAAUUUCUGUGUAUUUGUACAAUUUCAAAAGUUCACCUCGCUGUUGAGUUCUAGUUUUAUUCCACUGUGGUCAGGAAAGAUACUCGAUAUAAUUUCAAUUAUUUUAAAUUUGUUGAGACUUGUUUUGUGGGCUAACAUAUGGUCUAUUCUGGAAAAUGUUUCUUGUGCUGAUGAAAUAAUGUGUUUUCUGAAUCUGUUGGAUGAAAUGUUCUGUAAAUGUCUCUUUGUUAGUCUAAAAUGCAGGGUUUUUUGUUUUUUUGAGAGAGUCUCACUCUGUUGCCCAGGCUGGGAGUGCAGUAGCAUGAUCUUGACUCACUGCAACCUCCACUUCCCAGGUUCAAGCAAUUCUCGUGCCUCAGCCUGCCAAGUAGCUGGGAUUACAGGUGCCCGCCACCACACCCAGCUAAUUUUUGUAUUUUUAGUAGAGACAGGGUUUUACCAUGUUGACCAGGCUGGUUUUAAACUCCUGGCCUCAAGUGAUCCGCCCACCUCAGCCUCCCAACGUACUAGGAUAACAGAUGUGAACCACCGCGCUCAGCCUAAAGUGCAGUUUAAAUCUAGUGUUUUGUUGUUGAUUUUCUGUCUAGAUGAUCUGUUCAGUGCAGAGAAUGGGGUGUUGAAUUCCCCAGCUAUUGUAUUGGUGUCUAUGUCUCCCUUUAGAUCUAAUAAUAUUUGCUUUAUAUUAUGUAUCUGGGCGCUCCAGUGUUGGGUGCAUAUAUAUUUAGAAUUGUUACCUCCUCUUACUGAAUUGAUCCCUUUAUCAUUAUAUAAUAACCUUUUUCUUUUUUUUAAUCGUUUUUUACUUGACGUCUGUUUCAUCUGAUACAAGUACAGCUACCCUGCUUGCUUUUGGUUUCUGUUUGCAUGGAAUAUCUUUUUCCACCCUUUCAGUCUAUGUGUGUCGUUACAGAUGAAGUGAGUUUCUUGUAGGCAACCGUAGUUGGGCCAUGUUUUUUAAUCCAUUCAGCCAGUCUAUAUAUUUUAAGGGGGGAAGUUUAAUAAGUUUACAUUCAAGAUUAUUAUUGAUAGGUGAGGACUUCUGUCAUUUUGUUAAUUAUUUUCUGUUUUUUUAAAUAUAUCCUUUGUUCCUUUCUUCCCCUCUUAUUGUUCAUCCUUGUGAUUGGUGGUUUUCUGUAGUGGUAAAAUUUGAUUCUUUUCUCUUUCUCCUUUGUGUAUGUGCUCUACCAGUGAGUUUUCUACUUUUUUGUGUUUUCUUGAUAGUAAUUAUCAUUUCACUUCCAGAUGUGGGACUCCCUUGAGCAUUUCUUAUAAGGCUGGUCUAGUGGUGAUGAAUUCUGUCAGUUUUUAUUUGUCUGAGACAUGUCAGGCAUUUAGCUUCAGGACCUGAUUCUAGUUCCCUGCCCUGUGGCAACAAGUAGAAACAGAUCCCUGGUACCCUGCUUAAGUAUUACACCAGCUAGAUGUGAGCAGAUGAGAAAAUCAAAUCCUUCUAUUUUGCCAGGGAUUAAUUCAUUCUCAGGAUUGUAAAUAUUACAUUUCACCUUUCACCUCACAGAACUGUAGAAUUAGGAGGUGAGCUGGGCAGCCUGCCCAGCAAGACAUUAUGAUGUAUACAAUACAGUGCACUACUAAGGAUGUGUCUUUAAAGGCAUUUACAGCACACAGUUUUUUUUUUCCUUAUAAUUUUGCUGCUCUUUAUUUGUAGUAGUAGAUAAGGAAUUAAGAAAGCAAAAAUGAGUGCUUUGACUAGGUCUUUUGCCUUUGAAAGUAGCAUUAGUAAAAUCCCCUCUUCUUUUUUAUUCUUAUAAAAUUUACCCAAUUCACUCUGUCCCCCAGCCCAUCUGUGUUCACUUGCUGUUCUUGCUGCUCUCAGUUUUUAAAAGCUUAUUCUAAAAUUACAUCAAAGCAACCCCAUUUUGACAAAAUUAGAAUUCUGGUAGGAAACGCUUGCCAUGAGGCUGUGGAGAGAGGCCCAGCAAGACUUUUGUAUUUUAUUUCAACCUCUGUCGGUUAAACCUACAAUUCGGCAGAUGAUAUAAUUACCUCCCUGGGGCAGGUCUCUAUCUCUGCCUUGGAGAAAUAGCAAAGUCCAAAGUAGUCUCCUCAUUCAAAGAUGUUGCAAACGAAGGCUGUUUUGAUCUUUAUGUAUUAGCAUUUGGGUGUUAAUCUUUCUGGAGCUCCUGACAGAAAAUUCCUUUAAAUUUAUUAUAUAAUUCUAAAAUAUUGGACAUAUUUGUUUCAAGCAUCUGUCAGUAUCCUUACUCUUUCCAUUUCACUCCCCACUGCCUUAAUUAGUCAUCAGGUCCUACUGAUUUUUAACUCCUAAGCAUUUCUCAAAUCUGUCUCCUCAGUAUGUAUUGUUGGUUAUAUAACUCCAUCUCCAUUUUCACUGUGCUGCUUUAGACUAUCUUUUCUUGUCUAGAUUAGUGCCUGGCUUAUAUUAUGGGCUUCAUAAAGUGGGAUCAAUGAAUGAAUGAUUCAUAAUCUGGACAACUGCACUCUAACACCUAACUGGAAAAAAAAAAAUCUUAAGAUCUAUCUUCCAUGUAAAAGCAUCUAUCUAAAAUGCAAAUCUUACUUUGAUAAUCUCCAGGUUAAUAAACCUCUUAGACGGCUCUCAGGCCUCCCCAAAA